AGAGCUGGGUCAGAGCUCGAGCCAGCGGCGCCCGGAGAGAUUCGGAGAUGCAGGCGGCUCGGAUGGCCGCGAGCUUGGGGCGGCAGCUGCUGAGGCUCGGGGGCGGAAGGUCUGUGUGUGACAAGAGGGACGGUGGGCAGCGGCCCUGGGCACCGGGCCGGCACUGAACCCCCACUCCCCACAGCUCGCGGCUCACGGCGCUCCUGGGGCAGCCCCGGCCCGGCCCUGCCCGGCGGCCCUAUGCCGGGGGUGCCGCUCAGCUGGCUCUGGACAAGUCAGAUUCCCACCCCUCUGACGCUCUGACCAGGAAAAAACCGGCCAAGGCGGAAUCUAAGUCCUUUGCUGUGGGAAUGUUCAAAGGCCAGCUCACCACAGAUCAGGUGUUCCCAUACCCGUCCGUGCUCAACGAAGAGCAGACACAGUUUCUUAAAGAGCUGGUGGAGCCUGUGUCCCGUUUCUUCGAGGAAGUGAACGAUCCCGCCAAGAAUGACGCUCUGGAGAUGGUGGAGGAGACCACUUGGCAGGGCCUCAAGGAGCUGGGGGCCUUUGGUCUGCAAGUGCCCAGUGAGCUGGGUGGUGUGGGCCUUUGCAACACCCAGUACGCCCGUUUGGUGGAGAUCGUGGGCAUGCAUGACCUUGGCGUGGGCAUUACCCUGGGGGCCCAUCAGAGCAUCGGUUUCAAAGGCAUCCUGCUCUUUGGCACAAAGGCCCAGAAAGAAAAAUACCUCCCCAAGCUGGCAUCUGGGGAGACUGUGGCCGCUUUCUGUCUAACCGAGCCCUCAAGCGGGUCAGAUGCAGCCUCCAUCCGAACCUCUGCUGUGCCCAGCCCCUGUGGAAAAUACUAUACCCUCAAUGGAAGCAAGCUUUGGAUCAGUAAUGGGGGCCUAGCAGACAUCUUCACGGUCUUUGCCAAGACACCAGUUACAGAUCCAGCCACAGGAGCCGUGAAGGAGAAGAUCACAGCUUUUGUGGUGGAGAGGGGCUUCGGGGGCAUUACCCAUGGGCCCCCUGAGAAGAAGAUGGGCAUCAAGGCUUCAAACACAGCAGAGGUGUUCUUUGAUGGAGUACGGGUGCCAUCGGAGAACGUGCUGGGUGAGGUUGGGAGUGGCUUCAAGGUUGCCAUGCACAUCCUCAACAAUGGAAGGUUUGGCAUGGCUGCGGCCCUGGCAGGUACCAUGAGAGGCAUCAUUGCUAAGGCGGUAGAUCAUGCCACUAAUCGUACCCAGUUUGGGGAGAAAAUUCACAACUUUGGGCUGAUCCAGGAGAAGCUGGCACGGAUGGUUAUGCUGCAGUAUGUAACUGAGUCCAUGGCUUACAUGGUGAGUGCUAACAUGGACCAGGGAGCCACGGACUUCCAGAUAGAGGCCGCCAUCAGCAAAAUCUUUGGCUCGGAGGCAGCCUGGAAGGUGACAGAUGAAUGCAUCCAAAUCAUGGGGGGUAUGGGCUUCAUGAAGGAACCUGGAGUAGAGCGUGUGCUCCGAGAUCUUCGCAUCUUCCGGAUCUUUGAGGGGACAAAUGACAUUCUUCGGCUGUUUGUGGCUCUGCAGGGCUGUAUGGACAAAGGAAAGGAGCUCUCUGGGCUUGGCAGUGCUCUAAAGAAUCCCUUUGGGAAUGCUGGCCUCCUGCUAGGAGAGGCAGGCAAACAGCUGAGGCGGCGGGCAGGGCUGGGCAGCGGCCUGAGUCUCAGCGGACUUGUCCACCCGGAGUUGAGUCGGAGUGGCGAGCUGGCAGUACGGGCUCUGGAGCAGUUUGCCACUGUGGUGGAGGCCAAGCUGAUAAAACACAAGAAGGGGAUUGUCAAUGAACAGUUUCUGCUGCAGCGGCUGGCAGACGGGGCCAUCGACCUCUAUGCCAUGGUGGUGGUUCUCUCGAGGGCCUCAAGAUCCCUGAGUGAGGGCCACCCCACGGCCCAGCAUGAGAAAAUGCUCUGUGACACCUGGUGUAUCGAGGCUGCAGCUCGGAUCCGAGAGGGCAUGGCCGCCCUGCAGUCUGACCCCUGGCAGCAAGAGCUCUACCGCAACUUCAAAAGCAUCUCCAAGGCCUUGGUGGAGCGGGGUGGUGUGGUCACCAGCAACCCACUUGGCUUCUGAAUACUCCCGGCCAGGGCCUGUCCCAGUUAUGUGCCUUCCCUCAAGCCAAAGCCGAAGCCCCUUUCCUUAAGGCCCUGGUUUGUCCCGAAGGGGCCUAGUGUUCCCAGCACUGUGCCUGCUCUCAAGAGCACUUACUGCCUCGCAAAUAAUAAAAAUUUCUAGCCAGUCA